GUCACUGCGCGAGGGAAGAGGGAAGAGGAUCCAGGCGUUAGACAUGUAUAGACACAAAAACAGCUGGAGAUUGGGCUUAAAAUACCCACCAAGCUCCAAAGAAGAGACCCAAGUCCCCAAAACAUUGAUUUCAGGGCUGCCAGGAAGGAAGAGCAGCAGCAGGGUGGGAGAGAAGCUCCAGUCAGCCCACAAGAUGCCAUUGUCCCCCGGCCUCCUGCUGCUGCUGCUCUCCGGGGCCACGGCCACCGCUGCCCUGCCCCUGGAGGGUGGCCCCACCGGCCGAGACAGCGAGCAUAUGCAGGAAGCGGCAGGAAUAAGGAAAAGCAGCCUCCUGACUUUCCUCGCUUGGUGGUUUGAGUGGACCUCCCAGGCCAGUGCCGGGCCCCUCAUAGGAGAGGAAGCCCGGGAGGUGGCCAGGCGGCAGGAAGGCGCACCCCCCCAGCAAUCUGCGCGCCGGGACAGAAUGCCCUGCAGGAACUUCUUCUGGAAGACCUUCUCCUCCUGCAAAUAAAACCUCACCCAUGAAUGCUCACGCAAGUGUAAUGACAGACCUGAAUAAAAUGUAUUAAGCAGCAGUGAUCUUUCCUCUCCUCCUUCCCAAGUCAUUUGAAAAGUGUUUGUUAUUUAAAUUCCAAUAAUGCCCAAUACUGACGUGUCUUGAGUAAUUUGGAACCCAAAGUGAAGAUCUUUGAUAAAGAUUUUUUUGUGGUUCGACUGGACUGUGCUGAGUGCGGGCACUGGGCUUUUCUUCUGAUGUUCAUUAUGGUGCUGGGAAGCUCUGUCUUUGAUUUAAAAUAAAAUAGCUAAAGGCUACACAAUUAAGAGUUCAGAAUAACAUCUUAUUUCAGUUUAUGAAUUGAUAUGAAUUGUCUAAUUUAAAAAAUAUUUCCCUCACAUUAAAAGCAAAUUUUUAA